GUGGGAGACGCUAUCGCAAGAUGGCGUCUGCGAGGCCGCGGGAUGCGGAGUGAGCGCGCCCCGCCGGGGGCUGUGCGAGGCUGCUGCUGCUCUCCCCGUCGCCGCCGCCGCCGCCGCCAGUGCGGCGCCGCCUCUCCGCCAGCCACUGCGCCGCGGCCAAGCCUCCUGCCUCGCAGGUACCUCCUCCCGCGCGCACGCUCCGCGCCUGAUGGCAGCGACAAGUGCCGGCUCGCGGAGAGCUAGCGGGGCUCCCUGGGCCCGGUGCGCCCGACAAUAACGCGUGAAUAACUUUUUCUUGCAGCGGUCCCCCGCGUCCCGGCCUGCAGCCUCCCCGGGCGCCGGCGCCCCCAGCACGCCCCAUCGGGCACCCCACUCUCUCCGAGGUGUGGGUGCGGCGGGCUGAUGAGGUGAUCCCUAGCCCGCCUGGGAGGAGCGCCUGGACUCGCGGGCGGCGGCGAGCGCCUUUACAAUGGCCCUGACCCUGUUUGAUACAGAUGAAUAUAGACCUCCUGUUUGGAAAUCUUACUUAUAUCAGCUACAACAGGAAGCCCCUCAUCCUCGAAGAAUUACCUGUACUUGCGAGGUGGAAAACAGACCAAAGUAUUAUGGAAGAGAGUUUCAUGGCAUGAUCUCCAGAGAAGCAGCCGACCAGCUCUUGAUUGUGGCUGAGGGGAGCUACCUCAUCCGGGAGAGCCAGCGGCAGCCAGGGACCUACACUUUGGCUUUAAGAUUUGGAAGUCAAACCAGAAACUUCAGGCUCUACUACGAUGGCAAGCACUUUGUUGGGGAGAAACGCUUUGAGUCCAUCCACGAUCUGGUGACUGAUGGCUUGAUUACUCUCUAUAUUGAAACCAAGGCAGCAGAAUACAUUGCCAAGAUGACGAUAAACCCAAUUUAUGAGCACGUAGGAUACACAACCUUAAACAGAGAGCCAGCAUACAAAAAACAUAUGCCAGUCCUGAAAGAGACACAUGAUGAGAGAGAUUCUACAGGCCAGGAUGGGGUGUCAGAGAAAAGGUUGACAUCACUUGUUAGAAGAGCAACUCUGAAAGAAAACGAGCAAAUUCCAAAAUAUGAAAAGAUUCACAAUUUCAAGGUGCAUACAUUCAGAGGGCCACACUGGUGUGAAUACUGUGCCAACUUUAUGUGGGGUCUCAUUGCUCAGGGAGUGAAAUGUGCAGAUUGUGGUUUGAAUGUUCAUAAGCAGUGUUCCAAGAUGGUCCCAAAUGACUGUAAGCCAGACUUGAAGCAUGUCAAAAAGGUGUACAGCUGUGACCUUACGACGCUCGUGAAAGCACAUACCACUAAGCGGCCAAUGGUGGUAGACAUGUGCAUCAGGGAGAUUGAGUCUAGAGGUCUUAAUUCUGAAGGACUAUACCGAGUAUCAGGAUUUAGUGACCUAAUUGAAGAUGUCAAGAUGGCUUUCGACAGAGAUGGUGAGAAGGCAGAUAUUUCUGUGAACAUGUAUGAAGAUAUCAACAUUAUCACUGGUGCACUUAAACUGUACUUCAGGGAUUUGCCAAUUCCACUCAUUACAUAUGAUGCCUACCCUAAGUUUAUAGAAUCUGCCAAAAUUAUGGAUCCGGAUGAGCAAUUGGAAACCCUUCAUGAAGCACUGAAACUACUGCCACCUGCUCACUGCGAAACCCUCCGGUACCUCAUGGCACAUCUAAAGAGAGUGACCCUCCACGAAAAGGAGAAUCUUAUGAAUGCAGAGAACCUUGGAAUCGUCUUUGGACCCACCCUUAUGAGAUCUCCAGAACUAGACGCCAUGGCUGCAUUGAAUGAUAUACGGUAUCAGAGACUGGUGGUGGAGCUGCUUAUCAAAAACGAAGACAUUUUAUUUUAAAUUUUUAAUUUGAGGGGAAAAGAAAUGUUUUACAGAUGAAGGAAUGUUUUAUAGUAAUUUAAUUUGCUCCUGUAGCUGCAUUAUUUCUUGAUUAGAGGUUUGGGCAUAUAACCAGAUUAAAGUGAAGGAACUUUCUGUUGUUUUUGUAGCACCGCUCAGCUGUCUUGUAAAACAGUGAACACACGCUUUCUGGUUCUAGUAAUCCUGGGUGUUUAUCACGUUCAGAGAAACUCAAGCUAUUGCAUGAUUAGCCCCCUAUCUGGCAAGGAAACCCCAUACAGAAGAAACAACAAACCUGCGCCUGCACCGCCUCUGCGUCCUGGGUAGUCUGUGCUUGUAAUCCAGCAUGUUUCACAGAGUAAGCCUGUUGUGACUUUGCUUUUGGGGUCUAUGUCAUUGGUUUCUGAUGCUUGUACAAACACGCACACACAAAUGGAUAAAACAGCACCUCUGGCUGUUACAUUACCAUAAACCAUAUCACAUGCCUACAUUUUACAAAUGAUUUCUGGUUUCUCUUAGUUCUUCUCUAACAUAGUACUUUCUUUCCAGCAAAAGCAAAAUGUGUUUUCAGAUUUGUUACUUUAAUAAAGGUUAUCCAUACCAAUAAAAAGUGUACAACACAGCAUUUUCUGUUAAAUUAUUAUUGGUUUUCAGUUGUAAUUUGGUAUUUUUUCUGGCAUGCGUUUAUUAAUUUAUUAAAUUGGCUUUUAGAAAUAAAAAAUAUUGAUAGCUUACUUUUUUCUCAUAAGAAUAUUCGGGAAAAUGUGUUUGGCCAUUUAUUAAAUACUGAGUACUUCUUCUGACCUCUUUUGUUUACUGUUAAAAGUGAUAAGCUUCUAAAAUAAUCAUUUAAAACUGCUUACAGUUAGAACAACCAUUAAUUCCAUUUAUUUUUCUUCUUAUAUUACUCUGGCAGAAAUCUAGAAAAUAUUUUCUUGACAUACUUUUUAAUGAGAGGUUGGGCAGGAGUUCCUACCAGAGCUCUCAGAAGAAGAAAGAGGCUAACUAAAAAGAGUAACUUCUUCUAAACAUUUGAUUUGUCAAAAAUAUAUGACAUCAACAUGCAUUGAGCUGACAAUGCUGCCUGAGAGAUGAGCCCCAGAGGCCAACCUGGUGGCUGGAGAAGGGGUCUGCAGCUAGGGGCCAGGAGCCCAGAUUCUGGGCCUGGUACUACCACUGGCCACCUGUGUGGCUUGGAGCCAACAACCCUCCAGAGUCUGUUUCUGUGCCUAUCAGAUGAACACCUUUCUAGAACGAAAGUUCCAUCCUGUUUUCAAAUUUUUAACAAUAAAAGACACAUGUUCAAA